GCACUGUGCAGCUGCUCCAGUGAGGGCGCAGACUGUACUGGCCUGUGCGGAGCAAGGCGGUGUUUCUGACGCAUGGGGGCCAUGGAGCAGAGGAAGGGCUGGAUGCAUGAAGGAGGCGGGGUGCGGGGAGCGAGGGACCCGCAGACUCCAGGGCCACAGAUGCGUGGACCUAUUGGAGACCCUCAGGUUGUCUCCCCACCCCACGCAGAGAGGAAUGCGCAGCUGAAGAGAGAGGUGGGCAGCAGGCCCGGUCACCUGCCAGGUGACCACAUGGCCAGGUGCCGCCACCACUCGGGUUACCUGGCCGAUGACGAGGCCAGCCACUCCAUGUGCAGUGCACGGGUGCAGCUGCCCAAGAAGCCACUGGUCCCAGAAAUGCGGCCAGCCUGCAAGCCGGGCCGUGUGCCACACCCACCAUCCACAUGUGGCAGCUCAGCACUCCAGGGCCAACGCCGAAACAAGAGGCACCCUCAGCCCUUUGGCCACUUUCUGGAUUUCCUAACUGAGAGCCAGGUCCUGGACAGCCUGGAGACAGUGGUGGAGAAGGCGACUGAGCGCAUGGCUGCCAUGAAGACGGAGGCUGGGGUGCCGCUUGUGGAGGUGCAGGACCCAGUGGAGGUGCCAAGUGGUGGACGGCGGGCACAUGCCCGGCCCAGCCUCAGCACCGUACACCGGCACCGUGUACGGCCGACCCUCUGCACUGGACACCCCAACAACUACCCAUCCAGCUCCAGCUCCAUGUCCAACUGCCAUAGCAGCCUCAUGGCCGGCUGUCUGGGCUCCCACAGCCGGGACAGUGACCUAGGUGCCCAAGGCUCAUUGCCACCUGUGAGGGACAAACUCCUGCUGGAGAAGAACCUCAAGCGGCUGCUACAGCUGGAGAGGGAAGGGAAAGGCCUCAGUCAGUCCUGCUCCCAGAGGGACUCCCUGCUGUGGGAUUCGCUGGGUAGCCAGACCAGCUUUCAGUGGACACAGGAGCAGCCCUUGUCCUGGUUCUCAGGGCUGCUGGGCUCAAGCUCUGGCGUGCCUGAAGCAUCAGAGCCGAGGCCUGGAGAACAGGAGCCAAUCUUCCGCAAGCGAGAGUUCAAUAAGGAGAUCAAGUCAUUACUGAGCCAGCUGGAGUCCCUCGACCUGCCUGGCUACUGUCCGCUCCGUGAGCCCCAUCGCACGCUGAACUUCCUGGCUGACCACCGCCUCUUCCCUGCCCUGCAAAGCGUGGUCAGCCAGGCUGUGGAUAAGCUCCGUGGCGCCCACUGCCGCGACGGCCGUCCUCUGUUCCCCACCAGCUUGGAGCCCACCUCAGAUCUGCCGCCUCUGGGCUCUGAGCCAGCUAAACCCACCAAUGGCGGGCAGCCCUAUGCUUCCCCCCGCCCCACAGUCUCCAGCCCCAAGAUGCUUCAGAGAAAACGCAAGGACAGAGGAGGCUCCCCCUCCAUGUCUAGUGCCCAGGUGGCCACCAGAUUCAAACUCAAGGUGACACCCACGGAGAAGCCCAAUGUCCCCAGCCCCUCACUCCACUCCAGGGAGGAGGCACCUGACUCAGAUCCCAAAUUACAAAACCCACCUGUUUCCCUGAGCUCCAGCCAGAGGGCCCAGCCCUGGCAGGGCCUGCACCUCACCCUGCCCACGCCAGGGAUUGUGGUGGAGGUGGCCUGCAGCCAGGGCCACCUCAGGGGCCCUGUCACACCUCCACUUUCCUCCCCCUACCCCCGCUCUUCCUGCUACCUUCUCCCUGAGCUCUCUCCAGUUGCCUCUUCAUCUCCCGCCUCACUGUGUCCAGAGGUGACCUCCUCAAAAGUAGGACCGGGCAUGAGUUUGCAGGAGAAGGGCUCCUUGACCCACCACUCCUAGCAGCCACUGUCACUAACAGAGCCCCUGCAGCAGCAGCAGGUUCACGAAGAAGAAGCCGCUGCCCUCCAUCUCGUCGAAGUCCAGCAUGUCUCACUUCUCCAACCGCCUUUAUGAGGAGCUCGCCGACUUCCUGACCCAGCAGGCAGCCUCCUUGGUCAUCCGCAAGUACGAGUUCGAAAAGGACCUCAGUAAGCAGCUGGGCUUCUUCUCCUUCCCCAUCACCCACGUGCUCAGGGACCUUUCCCUGGGCUUAAAGAAGGUAAAAGGCUCCCGCAUCCACCUGUCCUCGGAGACCCACCGGAGCUGCCUGCUGCGUAAACUGGAGGAGUCCAAAAGGGCCCGGCAGGCCUCCCGGCUCAGCACCUCCCACUGCAGCACAGAGACACCCUCUGUGCAGCAGGAACCAGCCACCCACACUGCCCAGGACCAGGCCACAGAGCCCUGCCGCUCCCUCUACACCAACUUGCCAGCCAGCCGGCAGCUCAGCCCUUUGGAGCCCAAGCUCUACAUGUCUGCCUGCACCGGCAUGGGUUCCAGUCCCCCCAAGUCCAAGGACAUGGACAAUGAGGGCCGUGAUAAAGCCGAGAUUGAAGAUGAAGAUGAGGAUGAGUUCAAGGAUGAAGACCAGGAUGAGGACAAGGAUGAGGAUGGAGUCUAGAGCCUCCCAGAGCCUGGAGAGGAGGCCUCGGUCAGCCACUCCGUGGACGUGGGCCACGGUGACCCACCAUGAAGUCCCCACUAGCCACUCGAUUCCCUGCUCUGUCAGAGUUGCUGCACAUCACACCAGCCCCUGCCAAGAGCAGGAGUCACCACAGGCUGAAUGCCCACGAGGAGCUCUGCUGAGACUCUCAAGGGAGCCAGUGAAAGAAAUAGAAAUAAAGCCUGUGUUGCUGGGACACAGGUUUGCUGUCCUGAGA